ACUGUUGCUAAGACUGUGGGUCGCCGGAGGUGGUGGGAGUUAGUUUUGGCAGCCCGGGCCUGAGAGAGGUCAAGGGUCAUUGCAGAGCCAGGGAGGAGAUGGUGAAGCAGACUAUCCAGAUAUUCGCGAGGGUGAAGCCCCCUGUCCGGAAGCACCAACAAGGGAUUUAUUCCAUAGAUGAAGAUGAAAAAUUAAUACCUAGCUUGGAAAUCAUCUUACCACGUGAUUUGGCAGAUGGGUUUGUGAAUAAUAAGCGAGAAAGCUACAAAUUUAAAUUUCAAAGAAUUUUUGAUCAGGAUGCAAACCAAGAGACCGUUUUUGAAAACAUUGCCAAACCAGUUGCUGGGAGUGUCCUGGCAGGUUACAAUGGUACCAUCUUUGCAUAUGGGCAAACAGGCAGCGGGAAGACAUUCACUAUCACAGGGGGUGCAGAGCGUUACAGUGACAGAGGCAUUAUCCCAAGGACACUGUCAUACAUUUUUGAACAGUUACAAAAGGACAGCAGCAAAAUAUAUACAACACACAUUUCCUAUUUGGAAAUCUACAAUGAAUGUGGUUAUGAUCUUUUGGAUCCAAGACAUGAAGCCUCCAGUUUGGAAGAUUUGCCGAAAGUGACAAUACUGGAGGAUCCUGAUCAGAACAUUCACCUGAAAAACUUGACUCUCCAUCAGGCAACCACAGAGGAAGAAGCUCUGAAUUUGCUUUUUUUAGGAGACACCAACCGAAUGAUUGCAGAGACUCCUAUGAACCAAGCUUCAACCCGUUCCCACUGCAUUUUCACCAUUCAUUUGUCAAGCAAGGAACCAGGAUCUGCAACUGUACGACAUGCCAAACUCCAUCUGGUUGACCUGGCUGGUUCAGAGCGAGUUGCAAAGACUGGAGUAGGGGGCCAUCUUCUAACAGAGGCCAAGUAUAUCAACUUGUCACUACAUUACUUAGAACAGGUUAUCAUUGCCCUUUCAGAAAAGCACCGUUCGCACAUUCCUUAUAGAAACUCCAUGAUGACCAGUGUCCUAAGAGACAGUUUGGGAGGGAACUGCAUGACAACUAUGAUUGCAACACUCUCCUUGGAGAAAAGGAAUCUUGAUGAGUCUAUAUCAACCUGCAGAUUUGCACAGCGAGUGGCACUCAUAAAGAAUGAAGCUGUUCUUAAUGAAGAAAUUAACCCCAGAUUAGUGAUUAAACGCCUACAAAAGGAAAUCCAGGAACUGAAGGAUGAACUGGCCAUGGUCACUGGGGAGCAGAGGACAGAGGCACUCACAGAAGCAGAGCUCCUUCAGCUGGAAAAACUAAUAACAUCCUUUUUGGAAGACCAGGAUUCAGACAGUAGAUUAGAGGUUGGCGCGGAUAUGCGUAAAGUUCAUCACUGUUUUCAUCAUUUAAAGAAACUAUUGAAUGACAAGAAGAUCCUUGAAAACAAUACAGUCUCCUCUGAAAGCAAAGACCAAGAUUGUCAAGAACCAUUAAAAGAAGAAGAAUAUAGAAAGCUACGAGAUAUUCUGAAACAGAGAGAUAACGAAAUCAAUAUCCUGGUCAACAUGUUAAAAAAAGAAAAGAAGAAAGCUCAGGAGGCUCUCCACUUGGCUGGCAUGGAUAGACGUGAAUUCAGACAGUCCCAGAGCCCACCCUUCCGCCUAGGAAACCCAGAAGAAGGUCAAAGAAUGCGACUAUCCUCAGCUCCCUCACAGGCCCAGGACUUCAGCAUUUUGGGGAAAAGAUCCAGUUUGCUCCACAAGAAAAUAGGAAUGAGAGAGGAAAUGUCAUUAGGAUGCCAGGAGGCUUUUGAAAUCUUCAAGAGGGACCACGCUGACAGCGUUACCAUCGAUGACAACAAACAGAUUCUGAAACAGAGAUUUUCUGAAGCCAAGGCCCUGGGAGAAAGUAUAAAUGAAGCAAGAAGUAAAAUUGGUCACCUGAAGGAAGAAAUCACCCAGCGGCAUAUACAGCAAGUAGCCCUAGGAAUCUCGGAAAACAUGGCCGUGCCUCUGAUGCCAGACCAGCAGGAGGAGAAGCUGCGAUCACAACUGGAGGAAGAAAAGAGAAGGUAUAAAACAAUGUUCACUCGCCUGAAAGCCCUGAAGGUGGAGAUCGAGCACUUGCAGCUGCUCAUGGACAAAGCCAAGGUGAAGCUACAGAAAGAGUUUGAAGUCUGGUGGGCAGAGGAGGCCACCAACCUGCAGGUAAAUUCUCCAGCAGUGAAUUCACUCGAUCACACGAAGCCAUUUCUCCAGACAUCUGACUCCCAGCAUGAAUGGUCCCAACUCCUCUCUAACAAAAGUUCUGGAGGCUGGGAAGUCCAAGAUCAAGGCACUGGCAGAUUCGAUGUCUGUGAUGUGAAUGCCAGGAAAAUCCUGCCCUCGCCUUGCCCCAGUCCACACAGCCAGAAACAGAGCAGCACCAGCACCCCACUGGAAGACAGCAUCCCCAAGAGGCCAGUGUCGUCCAUCCCUCUCACCGGAGACAGCCAGACGGACUCGGACAUCAUCGCCUUCAUCAAGGCCAGACAGAGCAUUCUGCAGAAGCAAUGUUUGGGAAGCAAUUGAAUUUCCAGGAAAUAUCCAUCCAUGAAUUAUGCCAGCAAGAAUGAAGCACAGAUGAAGGCAGCGCCCCUCACUUGCUCUGGCUUCAGAAGUGAACUAUGGGCUGCUGGGAGCAACUAGUGACUUUGAUUCCCAUGGAGGGGACUGUGUUUCUUUAAGGAUGCUGACCUGGAGGCCACCGAGAGGCUGGGGCUGGGGCUGACCACAACAUCCUUCCUGUGGUUGCUGGAGCUGCUGGCAGGGCCAGGCAAGGCCAGAGUGCUAGGGGCAGGGUGAAGGCUUCAGCUCACUGUUGUAGUGACGUUUUGUGUAGAUCUUUAUAAGCUUUUGAGAAUGUGAAAUAGCACCAUCAAAAUAUAAUGUCAGAGGAUGCUCACACCAGUGGAAUGUGGGGGGAAUAUUUUUAUUUUUAACGAUUUGCCAGCUCUCUCCCUUGGCCCGUGCUCUGGUUUGGAAGCCCAGAAAUGGCCAUGACAGGUCCAGGCAGGAUGUCCCAGCCACAGGCAAGGCAGUGGAAUGCAGGGCAUCCUGAAGGCCAAUCCUGAUCUCCCAGACCACAUCUUUCACCAUCAGCCUCUUGGCCAGGAUGACCUGGAGGCAGUGCCUGAACAGCUGUGUCUCCAGGGAGCCAUCUGCCCUGCAGGGUCUAAGGACAUCAUAGCACCCAGAGAACAGUGGGCAGCUCCCAGGGGCUCUGCUGAGAGCUUGAGAGAGGGCAGUGUGGGUACCUUGGGCCUCACAACCUUCACCCAGCCACUUGGGAGGAUUUGGGCUGACACUCCCCACUUCCACAGGGAAAAACAUAGCUGCCUGGGGGUCUUGUCUCCAUGGGCCCUCUCCAUGACAGAUCCAAGGGAAGGUGGGCAGCCCUCAAGGAGGUUCUUGAAGAACUGCCCCCUGGGCCAGGGGGUUCCAACCCAGCUGCAGCCAGGGAGGGGCAGCGGAGGGUGAGCAGGAGUGGCACCUGGAAAUGAAGCUAACUGGAUAAAAGUGCUGGUCCACUGCUCCUGGUGUCUCUGUCCUAUAAAUACAGGACCUGAUGACCCUGGAGGGGAGCAGAGUGGUAAUAUAGUAUAAUUGGCUUGAUUUUCUUUUUCGUUUUUUAGGACUGGGUAACAGGAUCAUGCAGGAGAAGAUUAAACCAUUACAUUUCUAAGCUAGGCAGGCCCAUCGAGCUCCUCUAAUCCACACCCCUAUUUUAUAUAAUUAGAAGGCCAGAGUGAAGGGGAGAUUCAGCUUGCUGUUCUAUGCCACUGACAAAUGUCCCCUCUUCAGGGGGCUUCCCCUGACCACUCCAUCUCGAGUCACCCCCUAGUUAUCCCCUAUCCCAUUACCAUUUUUUCUGCAUCACUAUCUGACAUGUUAUCCUUCCGAACUUGCCUAUUUUUGAAAUACCUGCAACCCCCCAUAAUACUAAGAGCUCCAAUGCAACAGGGACCUGUUUGUCUUGCUCAUUGCUGUGUCCCAAGCACAGAGUCGCUGUUCAGUAAACGGUCCUUCAGUUCAUGAGUAGACGAGCCAGAACCCAGAUGUGUUUCUCAGGCUGGUGUCACUCUGACUUCCCCCAGGCUCUGACUGAAUCCCAUCGGGACAGGGGCCAGCAUCUCUGGUCCACUCCUGGCCCUCACAGUUCAAUGGAACAUAGUAAGCCCUCUGUAAAGUCUGUAGAACCAGAGGAAGACCAAAUUCUGAUUCUAGAAGCCUCCCCAAGAGUCCAUGGAACACACAUGUAACUGCACACACACACACACAUACACACACACACUCUCAAGAGCCCUGAAGAUGGCAUGGCAUUUGCCCCAGUCCCCUAUGUAGCAGCAGCAGUAUUCUUGGCAUGCCUUAGUGCCCUCAGCCCUCUAGAGCUGGGUAGAGUCUACUAACUUUUAUUUUCUUUUAUUUUUACUUUCUUUUAUUUAUUUUUUGAGAUGGGGGGGGUCUCUGUCAGCCAGGCUGGGGUGCAGUGGUGCGACCAUACCUCACUAGUCAGCCUCCAACUCCUGGGCUCAAGCCAUACUCAGCCUCCAACUCCUGGGCUCAAGCGAUCCUCUCACCUCAGCCUCCAAAGUAGCUGGAACUACAGGCAUGCACCACCACACCUAGCUCGUUUUAAAUUUUUUGUAGAGACAGGGUCUCACUGUGUGGCUCAGGAUGGUCUCAAAUUCCUGGCCUUAAGCGAUGCUCCCGCCUUGGCCUCCCAAAGUGCUGGGAUUGCAGGCAUGAGCCACAUACCCUGCCAGAGUCUUUCAACAUUAGAUCUCCCACUGAGACAUCAUCUCCUGGAUCCAAAGGCCUUACUGACAGAGAUGUGUGGCAUGGCCCCAUGCGGGGUGUGAACCAGCCUCCUGGGGCAAUCACUAAGACAGGAAAGGAAAUGAAGACAGAAAAACACACAACAUGGGAUCUGGGGCCACUGGUGUCCAGAGCAUAUGCAAAGUGUGUGCAGCAACUGGCCAAGGGGCCUUUUGCUCCGAACAUCCCCUAAUGGAAGCCCAGCCUUUGAUAUGGACACAUGCUUGACAGCAGUGCACCUUCCCAGAGUUCACUGGCCUCUGCAAAUGGGAGAAAUUGAUGCAAUGUUUUGAAAAGACUUUCCAGCAAUCCACCUGGGAUCAGUGGAGCCACGGAUGACAAGAAGUAUCUGAGUUCACUCUAGGCCAAAAUGUGGGAUUUUCAAAAACAUUUUCUGGAAAGCAGCCUAGCCAGUGACUCCAGCCCAGUCCCUGCUAGAAUUCAACUGGCUCUACCAAUCCCUUGACAAGAAGUAGGGUGGACGGAGGUUGGAGGAGGGAAGUUAAAAUGUAGCUUGCCCAGAUCUUGCUAAAAAGGAGUUUUAGAAAGCAGAUAGAGAAAUUGUGGUAUACUGAAUACAUCAUUUUAAUUCUUCACCACCAGUAUAGAAUUACACAUCCAAAGCUUUGUCAUGGCCCACUUUGACUAAUGUGGUGUUGGCAAACCUGAUCCAGGCAGAGGCUUGAAUUGUGCUCUCAUGGUUGAGCUUGCCUCUUGCUCCAGUGAUCUCUCUUGGGAUGAACAUGCCAUGGGUAGCUGCUGCCCCUUCAGCCUGGAACAUCCAGAGAGCAGACCUGAGCCCAGUCUACAGCCUGGAGCAGAGCCUCCCAGGCAAGCCCAGCCCAGAUCAGCUGAACUAUGGCUCACCCAAAGACCUAUUGGCAUGAGAAUAUAUGCUGCUUGUCAUAAACCACUGAGGUUUAGAGUGGUUUGUUAUAUAGCAUUAAUUGUAGCAAUAGCAGACUGGCACAGAAAUUGGAACCCAGAGACAGUAUAUGACUGGAUCUAGGAUUUCUCAGUGCAGAGUUCAUUGUCUCUCCAUGCAGCCUGUGGAAAGGCACUGAGAGCAUCCUGUAUAUGGAAAAGCAGGACCACCACCUACAGCCAUGAUGAAGCAACAAGGACCUGAUUUACCCUCCUGCUUUAAAUGACUAAAAAUGAGACAAAAUCCUCUAUACAAACCAAUGGUUUUCAGCCAUUGGAUAACAAGCAAUAUAGGGUAUGAUUGAUCCGCAAGAGAAGGGAAACAAGUGAGGGGAGCCCUAUGAUUGCUCCAACUUACUGCCUGCAGUGAGUUUUCAGGCUGCAGCCCAGGAAGGGGGAACCAGGUAGAGCCCAGUGGUUUCCCUGAGUUGAGGAAAUGGAGCUGGGAAUCCAGGGAGGACAAAGUGGCUUAAAUUUGCAAGGCAGAGUCCCAGGGAUGAGAGAGAGAGAAGGAGAGAGAGAGGAGAAAAAAGAGAGAGAAAGAGAGAGAGCAUGCUCUGGAGAUCUUCAGAGGGUUACCCUUGAGUCUUCAGCUAACUACCGAUCAACAUCUGCAUGUGAAGAAAUUACCCAAGGCAGGGGAAAGAACCACCAGGAGGAAGCAGGUGGAAUAAUUUCCUGAGAUAACACUGUGUUGGGAAGAGUUCAUGUUUCCAACAGCCAGAGUGGAGAAACCUCCCAAAACAGUCAUUGUAUAGAGACACAUAAGGUACUGCCUCAGAAGUGGGGCCAAAUUAGUCCUAGAUGAUAGAUUGCUCUGGUCCCACCUAACAAAGCUUAAAAAGCCAGCCCCAAAGGAGUCAAAUUGUUUCCAGUAAGUUUCCAAGUAACUUCAAUGAGUCCCAAAACAAAGCUUCAAAAUAUCUAAAGGAAUAUGAAAAACAAACCAAAAAGAAACCAGCAUCCAACAAUAUAGAAUCCACAAUGUCUGGUGUCCAUUAAAAAAUAAUCAGGCAUGCAAAGAAGCAGGAAAAUAUGGGCCAUGAGAGGAGAAAAAACCAUCAAUAGAAAUAGAGGCCGGGUGUGGUGGCUCACUCCUAUAAUCCCAGCACUUUGGGAGGCCGAGGCAGGAGGAUCACCUGAGGUCAGGAGUUCAAGAACAGCCUGUUCAACAUGGGGAAACCCCGUCUCUACUAAAAAUACAAAAAAUAGCCGGGCAUGGUGUUGCGUACCUGUAAUCCCAGCUACUCAGAGGCUGAGGCAGGAGAAUUGCUUGAGCCCAGGAGGCAGAGGUUACAGUGAGCCGAAAUUGUGCCAUUGCACUCCAGCUUGGGCAACAAGAGUGAAACUCUGUCUCAAAAAAAAAAAAAAGAAAAAACAAAUAGAAACAGCCCCAGGCAUGGCACAGUUGAUAGAGUAAAUAGACAGAAACAUUUUUUAAAAUGCAAUGGGUGUGUGUUUCAAAUCUAGGCAGAAAAAAUGCUCCUUGUAAUUCCUUAAACAUAAGCAUGUCUCAUUCAUCUGGUCAUUGUUUUGACAAGGAUGUGCCAUCCAUUGUGCUAAGUUCUGAGGAGUCAGAGGUGACAGAGACAGAGAAAGUGCCAGCAUUCUUGGAACCUUCUAACGAAGGAGAGGGACAAGCCAGGCAUGGUGGCUCACGCCUGUAAUCCCAACACUUUGGGAGACUGAGGCUGGCGGAUCACGAGGUCAGGAGUUUGAGACCAACCUGGCCAACAUGGCGAAACCCCAUCGCUACUAAAAAUACAAAAAUUAGCUGGGUGUGGUGGUGCGCACCUGUAAUCCCAGCUACUCUGGAGGCUGAGGCAGGACAAUCACUUGAACCCUGGAGGCAGAGUUUGCAGUGAGCUGAGAUCGUGCCACUGCACUCCAACCUGGGCAACAAGAGCGAGACUCCUUCUCUGAAAAAAAAAAAAAGAGAGGGACAAUAAACAAGUAAGCAAGACAAUCUGAUUAAGAAGGAGUUGGGGUUAGCUGGGCAUGGUAGCAAGCGCCUGUAGUCUCAGCUACUCGGGAGGCUGAGGUGGGAGGAUCCUUGAACCCAGGAGGUUAAGGCUGCAGUGAGCUGUGAUCACACCACUGCACUCCAGCCUGGAUGACAGAGCAAGACCCUGUCUCAGAAAAAGAAGAAGGAGUUGGGGGUGGGGUAGGAUGGGCUUGGACUCACUAUCAAGGUGGGUGGGAGUGUGAGAACCCGGCAAGGUGCAAAGAGAGAAGCAGGGAAGGGAAGCUUAGGACAAUGAUGGCAGGUUGGGUAUUGGGUGAUGGGAAGAGGCAAAGGACGUGGAGCUUGGCAAAAAGGGGACUUGUGGGGAUUUGGGCCAUGUGAGCAUGUGGGGGAGACAGUGUUCCUUCCAUAACACGUGUCCAGGGACUGCCAGGGCUCCGAGGCAGAGCAGGUGUAGAGAGGUUGGCUGUGAAUGUUGGAUGUUGAAAACAUAUGUGUCAAAUGUGGGAGGAAAAAGCAGUGUUUCCUUGAAUACAAGCUCCUCCUCACCUUGCGAAAAGUGGCCUCUGAGUGUAGCCCUGAAUGCAUCUCCCAAGGAAUAGGAGGAAGCAGCAACCUUUUCAGAGUUAACUGCUUUAUUUGGGUUUUCCAUGGCCUCGUGCCAGCCAGCAGGGCUGAGCCAGUUUCACCCACACUGAGAGGGAACUCAGCAAAGAGCAAGCAGCAUGCCAGCUGGUACUCUUCCCUCUCCAUUCACUCAGCUCCUGAUCUCAGGAGGGCAGCCCCUCCCCAGGCCAGCACCCCUCCCCUUCUGGCCCCAGGUGUGGGAUGUUGUUGUUUUCUUUUCUCCGAAACAUCUCCUGGGUUUGUCUUUUCCAUCACUGUCUUUAGACUGAGGCAAGCAGUCCCCAUGCCUUCAGCCCCAUGUUUUGGGGGUAACCUGUGCUUUGACAUGCUUUGCUAAAAACUUUCUAAGUCUCCCUCUGGUGCUGGGACCAGCCAUGACCAACAACGUCAUCCAUGCAGGCCACCCCUAACAUAGUCCAGGCCUCAUGUGGGUCUCAGUUCCCUUUUCUUCUUUCAGGAAGUUCUCCAGUGCAUGCAUAGGGUUGACCAGAUGUCCCAAGGUGCUCUAGGACUUAUGCCUAUGAAGCUGUUUUAGGGCUUCCUAGUCAGUCCCUGGUUCCAGGAAAGCAGCCUGAUGAGGAGAUCAUUCCCGCUGGCUGGUGUGGCAUUUCUUUUAUGGCACUACCUGGGAUUGGGCCACCAGACCUGCGCUAACAUGCUGAUUUGAUGGACUCUUAACAUCAUAGGACAAAGAAUCGUCAUGUGAACCAAUUAGACAAUAAACAAAUGCCUAAGUGCC